GGGGAGACGGGCGGGCGCACAGCCGGCGCGGAGGCCCCACAGCCCCGCCGGGACCCGAGGCCAAGCGAGGGGCUGCCAGUGUCCCGGGACCCACCGCGUCCGCCCCAGCCCCGGGUCCCCGCGCCCACCCCAUGGCGACGGACGCGGCGCUACGCCGGCUUCUGAGGCUGCACCGCACGGAGAUCGCGGUGGCCGUGGACAGCGCCUUCCCACUGCUGCACGCGCUGGCUGACCACGACGUGGUCCCCGAGGACAAGUUUCAGGAGACGCUUCAUCUGAAGGAAAAGGAGGGCUGCCCCCAGGCCUUCCACGCCCUCCUGUCCUGGCUGCUGACCCAGGACUCCACAGCCAUCCUGGACUUCUGGAGGGUGCUGUUCAAGGACUACAACCUGGAGCGCUAUGGCCGGCUGCAGCCCAUCCUGGACAGCUUCCCCAAAGAUGUGGACCUCAGCCAGCCCCGGAAGGGGAGGAAGCCCCCGGCCGUCCCCAAGGCUUUGGUACCGCCACCCAGACUCCCCACCAAGAGGAAGGCCUCAGAAGAGGCUCGAGCUGCCGCGCCAGCAGCCCUGACUCCAAGGGGCACCGCCAGCCCAGGCUCUCAACUGAAGGCCAAGCCCCCCAAGAAGCCGGAGAGCAGCGCAGAGCAGCAGCGCCUUCCACUCGGGAACGGGAUUCAGACCAUGUCAGCUUCAGUCCAGAGAGCUGUGGCCAUGUCCUCCGGGGACGUCCCGGGAGCCCGAGGGGCCGUGGAGGGGAUCCUCAUCCAGCAGGUGUUUGAGUCAGGCGGCUCCAAGAAGUGCAUCCAGGUUGGCGGGGAGUUCUACACUCCCAGCAAGUUCGAAGACUCCGGCAGUGGGAAGAACAAGGCCCGCAGCAGCAGUGGCCCGAAGCCUCUGGUUCGAGCCAAGGGAGCCCAGGGCGCUGCCCCCGGUGGAGGUGAGGCUAGGCUGGGCCAGCAGGGCAGCGUUCCCGCCCCUCUGGCCCUCCCCAGUGACCCCCAGCUCCACCAGAAGAAUGAGGACGAGUGUGCCGUGUGUCGGGACGGCGGGGAGCUCAUCUGCUGUGACGGCUGCCCUCGGGCCUUCCACCUGGCCUGCCUGUCCCCUCCGCUCCGGGAGAUCCCCAGUGGGACCUGGAGGUGCUCCAGCUGCCUGCAGGCAACAGUCCAGGAGGUGCAGCCCCGGGCAGAGGAGCCCCGGCCCCAGGAGCCACCCGUGGAGACCCCGCUCCCCCCGGGGCUUAGGUCGGCGGGAGAGGAGGUAAGAGGUCCACCUGGGGAACCCCUAGCCGGCAUGGACACGACUCUUGUCUACAAGCACCUGCCGGCUCCGCCUUCUGCAGCCCCGCUGCCAGGGCUGGACUCCUCGGCCCUGCACCCCCUACUGUGUGUGGGUCCUGAGGGUCAGCAGAACCUGGCUCCUGGUGCGCGUUGCGGGGUGUGCGGAGAUGGUACGGACGUGCUGCGGUGUACUCACUGCGCCGCUGCCUUCCACUGGCGCUGCCACUUCCCAGCCGGCACCUCCCGGCCCGGGACGGGCCUGCGCUGCAGAUCCUGCUCAGGAGACGUGACCCCAGCCCCUGUGGAGGGGGUGCUGGCCCCCAGCCCCGCCCGCCUGGCCCCUGGGCCUGCCAAGGAUGACACUGCCAGUCACGAGCCCGCUCUGCACAGGGAUGACCUGGAGUCCCUUCUGAGCGAGCACACCUUCGAUGGCAUCCUGCAGUGGGCCAUCCAGAGCAUGGCCCGUCCGGCGGCCCCCUUCCCCUCCUGACCCCAGAUGGCCGGGACAUGCAGCUCUGAUGAGAGAGUGCUGAGAAGGACACCUCCUUCCUCAGUCCUGGAAGCCGGCCGGCUGGGAUCAAGAAGGGGACAGCGCCACCUCUUGUCAGUGCUCGGCUGUAAACAGCUCUGUGUUUCUGGGGACACCAGCCAUCAUGUGCCUGGAAAUUAAACCCUGCCCCACUUCUCUACUCUGGAAGUCCCCGGGAGCCUCUCCUUGCCUGGUGACCUACUAAAAAUAUAAAAAUUAGCUGGGUGUGGUGGUGGGUGCCUGUAAUCCCAGCUACAUGGGAGCCUGAGGCAUGAGAAUCACUUGAACUCGGGAGGUGGAGGUUGCAGUGAGCUGAGAUUGCGCCACUGCACUCCAGUCUGGUCGGCAAGAGUGAGACUCCGUCUCAAAAACAAAACAAAACAAAAAAACCACAUAACAUAAAUUUAUCAUCUCGACCACUUUUCAGUUCAGUGGCAUUCACAUCUCAUGUAACCAUUGCCACCACCAUCUGCAGAGCUGUUCCAGCUUCCUGAAUGGAAACUCUGGCCCCAUGAAACACUCACUCCCCAUUCCCCUCCCAACCCCUGGCACCCUCCACUCUACUUUCUGUCUCUAUGACUUCUCCAGGGACCUCAUGGAAGUGGAAUCACACAGUAUCUGUCCUUUUGUGUCUGUCUUAUUUUACUCAGCAUGGUGGCCCCAAGGUUCAUCCAUGUUGUAGCAUGUGCCGAAAUCUGCUUCCUUUUUUAAGGCUGAGUAAUAUUCCAGCACAUGGAUGGACUGCAUUGUGUUCAUCUAUGCUUUCCUCAGCAGACACCUGGGUGCUUCCACCUUUUGGCUGUUGUGAGUAAUGCUGCUAUGAAUAUGUGUGUGCAAAUAUCUGUGUGAGUCUUUGAGUAAAAUCGCUGGAUCACAUGGUAA